AGAAGCUGUCUAUCGGGCUCCAGCGGUCAUGUCCGGCAGAGGAAAGGGCGGAAAAGGCUUAGGCAAAGGGGGCGCUAAGCGCCACCGCAAGGUCUUGAGAGACAACAUUCAGGGCAUCACCAAGCCUGCCAUUCGGCGUCUAGCUCGGCGUGGCGGCGUUAAGCGGAUCUCUGGCCUCAUUUACGAGGAGACCCGCGGUGUGCUGAAGGUGUUCCUGGAGAAUGUGAUUCGGGACGCAGUCACCUACACCGAGCACGCCAAGCGCAAGACCGUCACAGCCAUGGAUGUGGUGUACGCGCUCAAGCGCCAGGGGCGCACCCUGUACGGCUUCGGAGGCUAGGCCGCCGCUCCAGCUUUGCACGUUUCGAUCCCAAAGGCCCUUUUUAGGGCCGACCA